ACUUCCGCUUACGCGCCCCACUUCCGCUUCCGGCCCCGGGCUGUGGUGACUGGCGGUGUGGGGUGGGUCAGAGGGCAGUAGGUACCUCCAGGCGGGAGCAGCGUUUGCACCGCGGUGGGUUCCUGCGAGCUGGUGCAGAGGGGCCCCAGCGGGCCGGCCCCGGGGCACAUGCGACGACCUCCACCCCUGGGCCCCACGACGGCCUCAGGGCCUGAAGGCAAUGUGCGAAACCUGCAGAAGCGGCAGGCGCCAGGGCCAGGCGCGGCGGGAGGCUGUGGCCCUGAGGCCGGGGGGUGCCGGGAAAAUAAGCAAAAGAGGAGAAUGGUGGCCCGGGCCACCCCUGGGAGAGGCGAGGUGGAAAGUGAUAAGUCGGUUGCAGCAUCAGGGGCUGGAAAGGCCGCAAGGCGUCAGGUGGAGGGGCGCAGGGGCCCGGUGAGCCCGUCAGACUCGUCAGACCCGCGAGGCCUAGAAGCAGCAAAGGAGGCUGAACUCCCCUUGCAAACGGAAAGACACACCAAGGAAAAAAGAAAAGUUACUGAAGCCUCAAGUGAUGAUCCACAGCCAGGGCUUGACUUGGUAAGAAAGGAAUCAUUAACCAGUUCGGAAUCUUUCCAAACAGUGGAAUGCUUGCAGUCUUUGGGUAAGGAAAGUAUAAUAGAAGGUAUUAAAAGAAGAAUUCGAAAUAAAAAACUUAAAAGCUUAGAAAACCCACCUCUCAAAAUAACCGAAAAUGAGGCUACACAAAAUAUUAAGGUUGAAUUCCAAGAUGAACUGUACAAGAAUACUCCAAAAUAUUCUUGUAAUAUCUUGUCACCUGAAGUAGAAAAUAAUUCCGUUUUAAAAUUACGUGAUUGCAAUUGUUUCCCCCAUUCCAAGGGUUGUAAUGAUGAAAACAACCUGCCAUAUAAACCUGAUGGUGGAUGUAUGCAUGUAGCAGAAAAUUUCUCAAAGAAAGAAAACCUUAGGAGUCUUGCAGAGAAGAGUGACACAAAUAGUAUUCCUCAGCUCUUACAAACAGAAGAAAAUGUAAUGGGAGUAAAUAAGUUACUACCAGAAGAGAGUGAUUUAUACCAAAGUAAAACCAAUGGCUUGCUUUCCUGCCUUCAACAUGAAAAAAAUAAAUAUUCAAUAGAGGAGAGCAGUGUUGGGCGAAAACCCAGGAAAAGGAUGAAGUUGUCUGAAAAAGCAGAUGAAACAGUUACUGAGAUGAACUUCUCUAAUGAGUAUAACAAGUCUGAGUUGAUGUUGCAAGAAAAUCAAAUGAUUGCUGAUGGUAAAGAAGCAGAGACUAAAAGUCCUUUAAAUGUUUUGAGAAAAGUAAGCCAUAAUACAGUCUCUUUGAUGGAUCAUUUAUUAAGUGUCCCAGAAACAGUAGAAAAAGAAACAAGUUCUGAACAUCAUGUAAAUGCUGUGUUUCAGAAAACCAUUGAACCACUUUUGAAAGAAGAAACAGAGAAUGCUUCAGAGCCGUUAGGUUAUGAAAGCAUGGCAUCGAAAGAGGAUUUUAAAUCGAUGAAAAGCUUCAUAGGGAAAUCACCUAAUGAGUACCAUAUUGAAAGGAGAUCUUCACGGGAAGACUUAAGAAGUGCAUCUGAAGAAUUGAAGUUAAGCUGUCAGAGAACAAUACCUAUGACUGGUAAAAGAACUUGGCCCUAUUAUUCAUGUGCUAGAAUAUCUGCCUGGUGUUGGAAAAAGGCUUCCUUGCCAGAAUCAAGUUACUUUCUUCGUGGGUCUCAGGAAAGUUGUAGGCAAGUUGAUGUCCCUAAACACCAAACAAACCAGACCCAUUUAACUGACUCCAAAUUAUUAUUACAAAGUUCCUUAACAGAAACAAACACUGAAUCUUCAAGUAAAGAAAAAUUAGAUUCUAAUUCUAAUUGUUUGUCUUCAGUUUCUGCAGUAGAACCUACUUUAAUGGUUAUAAAGGAACCUAUAAUCAAGGAUGAUAAAAAGAUAAAAUCAGAGGAACUGAGCAGAAGAGGGUCAGAGGUAAUUUCUAACACUACUGAAGAUACUCAAUUAACCAGUGAGACUCAAAGCUUAACGGGAAAUAAAAAAAAAGCUAGAGGAAAUUUAACGAAACUUAAUUUGACAGCGACUUCCAAAGAUGGUCAGGAAGCAAAUAACUCUGCAGGCAAAACUAUUCAUCGAAAAGCAUGCAUUGCUCAACAAACAUUUAUAGUUCCAGACUUGGUUAAAAUAUUGAACACAGGACGGCUGACUAAUUUUAAAAUUCCUUUACUUAAGAAUAAAUCAGAAAAAAGAAAAGAAGUAAAUGCCAAGUCAUCAGAGAGAGAAGCUUACAGUCCUCUAGAACUUCUGGACAAUUUAUCUGGAGCAGACGUAAGACAGAACAGGAGUAAAGAAAAUGUCUCCAUGAUGAUGUUAGGACCUCAAACUUUGAGCAUACGAAAUAGUGUAACUCCAGUGCAAGCUAGUUCUGACUCAUUCUACAAUAAGAAAUCCUAUAGUAUUUCUCCAAGCUUUACAAAGCAAGGUAACAAUAGCAAACCAUCUAAUCACGUCUCUGAACCAGGCAAUAUUGUUUCUAAUAAAGAAGUUGCUUCUCUCACAGUUGAAAAUAAUGCUUUUUCUUGUGAUCCUGGGUAUGUAGAGAAAAGUCCUUCCUUCUGCUGUAAUGAACAAGAAACAUUCCGACCAGUGUCCAGUGAAGUUAGGGGUAGAAAAAUAACUAAGAAUUUUUCAGAGGUAGGGUUUCCAGAUAUUCUUAAAGCAUAUGAAGAUGACGUCCUCUUAAUUGAUGUAAUUCAAGAUGACCCAGACCUCUUUGGAGUCUCCAAUGAAGGGGAGCUCUCAUUUACUUCUGAGGUCCCAAAGAUAAGCCAGGAGCCCAAUGUUGCUGGAGAGCACCAAUCAACAGACUCCAAGUACAUGGAAACUCCAGUAAAAAAAGAACCAAGUGAUGACUUAAGAGAACUUCCUGUACUGGACUGUGGAUGGAUAAAGCCAGACAUCUGUGCUUCCAACUCAGCAGAAAGUGAAAUAAAACGUGAUCCCAAAGAUGUAAACACUUCCUUAGGAGAAGUUGCUAAUGAGACCUCUGAAAAUGAAACACUGGGAGACUUCAGUGAACAAAUAAAAGGUUCAGACUUGGAUGAAAAGCAUAGAUUUACAGACAAAGUGAUUACCAAAGAAGAAAAAGAAAAUAUUUAUGAAGUUUGCAAAAGCAAAGAUUCUAGAAAUGCAGACUUUAUGGUCGGCGAAUGUCAAUUUGCAGUACCAGUCCCGAAACCUCUGUGUUUAUUAGUACCUCCUUUGAAUCUAAGUGGUCGUCAAGAAGACACAAUACUGAAUACCUGGAUGAAUGAUUUCAGAUUUCUGGGAAAACAUUCUGUCCUAAAGCUGCAGAAUCCUGAAACUUGUGAAAUAUUCAAGAGGGAAAAAAAUGUGGGGGUGUUCCAGAAGUCCCUAGGGUUGAUGAUACCCUAUAAAUAUUGCAAAUUUCAUUUUAAUACAUUACGUGGCUGUGAGCGACCACUGUGCAAGUUUGCUCAUGUGCCUGAACAAGGGGAUGAAAAGGUUUGCAUGGAUGUGUUUAAGAAAUAUAUAAAUAUCAAUGAACUGUGUUUGCUACAGCGUGCAGUAAACAUAUUUAUGGAGUACUACAGAAAGUUUCCCCCAGGUGUAUACUUUGAUUUACAAGUGCUAAAUGACCUUCUAAAUUCUUUACUCAAACAUUGUUUGUUGAAAGAAGUAUUUCAGAUAGUGAACCUCAGCAUAAUGGUUAAAAUGCUGCCUUCUCUGAAAAUAUUACUAAACAUAUUUGAGUAUGUGGCAACUAUGAAAUUAAGGAAUGCUGUACCUGCUUUAAUUGAUAUCUUUUGCAAGCUUGUUGAAGCCGGGAUGGUGCUUGACCCAGAGCACUUUAACUAUAUUGUUAAGCUUUUAUACCAAGUACAAGCUUCCAAACAAGAAAUAACUGCAGUUCUGGAAAUGAAAUCGAGGUUACAGAUGAGACGAUUUAAAAAGAACUGGAAGUGUGAUUUAGAUUCAGCCUUGAAUAAAUUAGAGCAUUGUAAAGAAAAAGGUGACUGGACCAAAUUGGGAAAAUUAUACAUUAACGUAAAAAUGGGCUGUGAAAAAUUUGCAGAUUUCCAGACAUUUUGUGCUUGCAUUGCUGAAACACUCACAAAAAACUAUGAAGAUGAAAGACCAGAUAUUCCCUUUUGUGAAUUUGCUGAAACAGUUAGCAAAGAUCCACAAAACAGUAAAGUAGAUAAAGGUGUACUGGGAAGAAUUGGAAUCAGUGCUAUGUACUUCUAUCACAAGCUGUUGCAGUGGUCCAAGGGAAGGAAGGUCUUAGAGAAACUAUAUGAAUUAAAAAUACACUUUACAAGUUUAAAAGGACUUAUAGGGCCUGAGAAGUUAGCAUCAAGAUGUCAAAUUGUGAAUGUUGCAGCAGAAAUUUUUCUAAAAAGUGGAAGCCUAGAUGGUGCCAUUUGGGUAAUGAGGGAGUCAGAGUGGAUAAUCAAUACGCCUCUGUGGCCUUGUGAUAGACUGGAUGUGCUUAAUCGACAUAAUUUACUCUGUACAAUUGCACAUGAAAUCUUAGCCAAGAGCCUUUAUAGACAGACAUUUGAAGUUUUGCAGAAUCUACCAGGUUUUCAAAAUUCCCAAGAAACUGUGGAAGUCUCACAAUAUAGCCUUCUUUUUAAUAAGCUUCUAGGUUCCUGUAUAGAAAGCAGUAGUCUUGGUAUGUCAUCCUCUGUGGCAGAAUUCAUGAUUUCAAAGAGCAUCCCUAUUGAUUUUUCCUUUCUCAGAAGAUUAAUUACUUCUUUAGGAAGGAGUCGUUUAUGGCUCAAAGCCAGAGCCCACUACAAAAGUGCUCUUUCCUUGGGUUGCUACCCACCAUUGGAAGGAAAUUUAUACCGAAAACUUCUUCUAAUUCCAUCUUAUUUAUCUGAGAUUGAAAUGCUCUUAGCUAUUGAAAUCUUCAUGGUAUCUAAUGCUAGUAGUAUUCAGAGUCCUGGAACUUCUACACAGAUACUGCAGAUAGUUUUGAAAAGGUGUGAAGACAACCAGUCUCGGAGCAAUGAUGAUUAUCAAGCUGCAGUAGAAAGGUUAAUUAUGGCUGCUCGUAUAUCAGAUCCAAAGCUUUUCGUUAAACACAUGACUGUCAAUGUUAAUAAGGAACAGGUUUAUAGUUUGGAACAUUGUUCUGCCCUGAAAUGGUUAAAAGAGAAUAUGAAGUGGGCUGGAAAGGUUUGGCUUUUCAGUAACCAUUAGCUAAUAAAGUCUGCUUUUUUUUUUUUUUUAGUUCAAGUAAUCAUUGUUGAAAAUAAAAGGCAAUAAAAAUAGACAGUUUUCACUAUA